GAGAGCCGCCCUGCGCCGGACUGGCUUGCGGGCCGGGCCGCCGCCCCCGGAGCCGCCCUCGCGCCGCCUCGGGCCGCCGCCGAGCAGUCGGGCCGCUGGGCGCCGCCGCGGGCGCCGGGAGCGAGCUGGGAGGGAGCCGCGCGCCUUUGUGCGCGCGCCGAGGUUUGCAUAUAACCACCUGUACAGAAGGGAGAAGAAAGAAACAGGAAAAACAAUGUAAAUUUCCACUUUAUUUGGAAGAAUGGGCUGACAAAAAAGUUUCAUGGACUAUAUUUUUGAAUUCAGGAGUCAUUUGGGAUUGACUUUUGUCUUUAAAUGAAAUCUUUAAGCUUUAAAAAUAUUUUAAAGGUAACAUUGUGUUCUGAGAUUCAUAAGAAAUAUGUGAUGGAAAGGAAUUCUUGUUUGUGGAACAAGGAAUAGCAGUGAUUGUACAACCGGGUGCAUGCUGGCUUCUUAAAGACCUUGCACUGAGAAAGUAAAAUAAGGGUUUUCCUGAGAAUCGUGAGUUGUGUUGAGUGUGUAUGUUCUUUUAAAAUAAAAUCGUUCUUUAGCCACAGAUUUGGCCACUGGACGCUUUUGUCAUUACAUACUUUUAUUUUCCUCUUGUAACAUUUUUGGACUUUUGAAUUCUCUAAUAUGCAAAAUAGAGGUCUUUGAGACAACCGUUUAGAAGUAGGUUGAUCAUUAGGAUGAUGCAAUACAUUUUGAAGUUAGAAGAAUCUACAAGAAGGAAGUUGUGGCUGUGUCCACUCAGGUGCAUUUUUGUUGCAGUUCCUGACACUCGGGGCGCUUUAAUCUGCACACACGCUCAGGGGAGUGUUGCGGUGCAGUAGUAGCCUGUGAGUGAAUGAGUCAUGCAUGCAGUCUGCUCUGAUGAUCGGCAUUCCUUCAGGAGUCGUGAUGUGUUUCUGUCUGCAAAAGUCAAACGAAGCUCCAAUAGGAAAUGUCACAAUCUCCUACCCCAGGGGACUGGAGAUCCCCUUCCUUGGGUGGUUAAAAAUGGACUUGAUUUGCGCUUCUGAGAAACUGACAUGUGAAAUCUUGUUCCUGAUGUGGGAGGAUGGACGCCGUCAUUCAUUCAUUCAUUCAUCGAAUCUUUCCUUUGACUGUUAAUUGUUUAAAAUCUCACAAGUAAAGGUGGAAAAGAGUUUUACUGAUUUUCUUUGGGAAUGGUGGAGGGGUAGAAGACUUCUCUCCUGAUGGAAAGAGGAAAGAUGAGGAAUAUGGCUUAAUGUUAUUCCUAACUUACCUUCUGCCCCUUCCCUCCAGAAUUCUGUGUGCAAGUGUUUUAAGGAAAUGAGUUGGGAGUUUGGGUAAGUGAGAUCUAGAUUUUGGGCAUUUGUAGAAGUCCCCGGCUAUCUGGGGGAGUUGUCACUCUUCUUUCAGCCUAGAGAAGGUGACUAUGGGUGCUAGUGUGCUGUGGGGCACACUCGGGGGUGGGAAAGCUGCUGUGGAGUGGGAUGUCCUCUGUGUGCAUCAUGGGGUCGAGUGUGGCCUUGGGAUGACCUCAUGAGACCUUGCUGCAUUUCCUUGUAUAGUUCCCUUGUCUAAUCAUGGCCUAUUUUUGCUUUUCCUUCUUGAAACAAACCAUUUUUCUCCCCUUUUCCUUUCUAGUUCAAGAAGGGCUGGGCCUGACCCAUCUGAAGUUUCCCUCACCCUAAGUACUUAGGAAACGUGCUGAAGAGGAAUGGACAGUCUUACCCAUCUCAUAUCCCUAAUUCCGGUACCCCAUCAGUGAAAGAAAGAAAGAUUAUUUGGCAAGCUGGAUUAGAUUGCCAUUUAGUUAUGGUGCAUGGACAAGGGGCUAUUUUAAGGUUGAUGGGGGAGGCUUUGCUUGUCAUUUACUCUCCAUUCACCAGACAUUCAGUGCCCGUCAUGUGCCAGGCACUGGGUUUACUGCUGUUAACAAGACUAUAAGGCAGGUGAGGAGGAUAUUUAAAGAACUGGGCUGGGUACAGUGGCUUGUGCCUGUAAUCCCAGUGCUUUGGGAGGCUGAAGCAGGAGGACUGCUUGAGGCCAGGAGUGUGAGACCAGCCUGGGCAACAUAGUGACCCUCAUCUCUACGAAAAAUUAGCUGGGUGUGGCAGCGCGCUCCUGUGGUUGAAGCUACUCAGGAGGCUGAGGCAGGUGGAAUGCUUGUGACCAAGAGUUUGAGACCAGGCUGGGCAACAUAGUGACCCCCAUCUCUACAACACAUUUUUAAAAAUUAGCUGGGAGUGGUGGUGCAUGCCUGUAGUCCCAGCUACCCUGGAGGCUGAAGCAGGAGGAUCACUUGAGCCCAGGAGUUCGAGGCUGCAGUGAGCUGUGAUCACGCCAGUGCACUCCAGUCUGGGUGACAGAGUGAGAGCCUGUCGCUAAAAAAUACAUAUACAUAUACAUAAAAAAGAAUUAUACAAAAUUACACAAAAAUUGUUUAAUUACAGUUAAGAGCUGGGAAGGGAAAGCACUGCUUGGUGAAUUAAGGUAUCUCAGAAAGAAUGAUGUCAAUGCCAUUGAAGGUGGGGGUUGGGUUUCUGAUGGUGGAAAUGUCAGGGUGGGUGGGUGCGGCGGGCCAUGGAGCUGCAUAGGGAUUUGCCUAGCGCCCAUCAGUUCAGAGCCUGCUGGUAGGGGCUUAGCUGAACAGAUGAGGUGGACUGUUCAGUUCUGUCUGGAAUUUGGCUGUGGGGUUCGGACACUUUGUCGCUUGGGAUUGAAGGUGGAUCGGGAAACCGUAUGGUUCUGUCCCAGUGUCCUUGCUGAAGGUAAACCUCAUGGCCAGUAGCCCUGGGAAGCCGGUUGUGGUAGGACGUGGUGUCCUGAGCUGGCCUGGAUUCCAGAAGUGAGGACUUGUAUCAUGCAAAGGGCACCCAACUACAGCUGUGCCCACCAGAGGUUUUGUUGCAAAUGAAAAGAUAAGAGGAAUUUGUGGGGAAAGAGUGAGAAGACUUAUUUAAGAACAUUAUUCGGACUCAGAUGAGCUGUAGGAAGGAAAACGGGGAGAGAGAUGCAGAAAAAGGAGGUAAUGUUGCUUUGACACCAGGUGAACUCUUGACUUUGGGACUGACUUUUUGUUUUUAAGUGAAAAUAAAUCUUUCAGCUUUAAAAAUAUUUAAAGAGUAAAAUUGAGUUCUGAGAUUCAUGAGAUGUAUGUGAUGGAAAAGAGUUUUUUUUUUUUUUUUUGUAGAUCAAGGAAUAGCAGUGAUCCCACAGCAGGGUACACGCUGGCACUGAGAAAGAAGAAGGGCUUCCCCACAAAGAGGGAGUUGUGUUGAGUGUGUAUGUUCUAUGGAAAUAGAAAUCAUUAUUCAGCCGCAGAUUCUACAUUCUUUUAUAUUCCCUGACCAGAGAUGUUUUACCAAAGGUGUGAGUUAAGCAUAUCUUUUUUUAAAAAACUGUAGAGAUGGGGUCUCACUAUGUUGCCCCGGCUGAUCUUGAACUCCUGGGCUCAAGUGAUCCUCCUGCCUUGGCCUCCCAAAGUGCUGGGAUUAUAGACGUGAGCCCCCAGGCCUAGCCUACCAAGGAUGUGAGUUAAGCACACGUGAAUAGUCCUAAAACAGGCCCUGUGGUCUGUAGUGGUGUUGGGGGCGUGUGUAAGUCACAUGGGUUGGAGACAAUAAUGUUUCCUCCACACAGCAAAGUCUUGGGGUUUCUGCUGUGGCAGAGAGACUGGGGUGUAAGAACAGCACCCCCUUAGAGGCUGUGAGAGGGCAGGGGACCCUCUGGGCUGCUCAGCAGGCCUCUUCCUGGUGGGGCUGCUUAAGUCCUUAGCAGUCGGGAGACUUAGAAGUCUUGAAGUGGGGGGGGACACUGAGCCCCAGCAACCCUCAGGUUAUGUAUGUGUUGUCAAGUCUCCCGUAGAAACAAGGUAGAAAAAAUGCAGGUUGCAGACUGGCUCUUCCGACCAUGGCAGGUUUAGGUGCAUGAGGUUAGAGGGUUGUGCCUCCUCAUUCUCUCUCUCCUUUCUGUUGUCAGUGCUGACUUGAAUUAUGCUGGAACAUCUCCAGGUGACAGCCCUGCCUGGCCACAGCCUGGGCCAGAGGAGUGGAGUUGCUGAACGGAGCAAGGUGCUGUAGGGGAAAGGUGUGGAGCUGUGAGCCUGGCCUCUCAGGGUGAGGAUCCAGGCCCCAGCUCUUUGACCUCCAGCAAGUCCCGUAACCCCUUGAGCUCUAGUAUUCUCAUCUGUGAGGUCGCCUGGGUUAUAUGCACCUCCCAUGCAUGGUGGGGACAUGUGGUCCCUGAGAUUUGGCAAAUGAGGGGUGUUUAUGCUGUUAUGCCAGUGCCCACAGCCUUUCAAAAAAUGUUCUUUACAAAAUGUUACUGCGAUAAGAGCACUUAACAUGAGAUCUACCUUCUUAACAGAUUUUUAAGCGUACGGUGUUUUAUUGUUGACUGCAGGUGCAGUGUUGUAGGGCAGCUCUCUAGAGCUUAUUCCUCUUGCUGAACUGAAACCUUGGGCCCAUUGAUUGGUAACUCCCCAUUUUCCCCCACUGCAGUCCCUGACAACCACCAUUCCACUCUUCAAGUCUAUGAGUUUAGCUACUUAGAUGCUUCAUCUAAGAGGAGUCACAUGGUAUUUGUCCUUCUGUGCCUGGCUUCUUUCACUUGGUCCUCCAGGUUCAUGCAUGCUCGUGCUUGUGGCGGAACUGCUUCUUUUCUAAGGCUGCCUGGUAUUCCACUGUAUGUAUAUUACCACAUGUGUUUACCCAUUCAUCUGUCCUUGAUGGUUAAGCUGGUUCCACAAAACUCCUAGAAGAAAACAUAGGGGAAGAGGUUCAGGACACUGGUCUUGGCAGUAAUUACGCGGCUGCCACGCUAAAAGCACAGUCAACAAACCCAAAACUAAACCAGAUUGCAUCGAACUAAAAAGCUUCUGCACAGCAAAGGAAACAGUCAACGGAGUGAAAAGGCAACCUGUGGAAUGGGGAAAAAUGUUGGCAAACUACAUAUCCAAUAAGGGGUUAAUAUCUGAGAAGUUUAAGGGAUUUCCGCAAAUCAACAGUAAAAAAAUGAAGAACCCAACUAAAAAAUGGGCUAAGGACUUAGACAUUUCAACUCGGAGUUUUUUUUUAUUAUUUUGUCUUUUUGAGACAGAGUCUCACUCUGUCACCCAGGCUGGAGUGCAGUGGUGCCAUCUCGGCUCACUGCAACCUCCACCUCCUGGGUUCAAGCGAUUCUCCUGCCUCAGCCUCCUGAGUAGCUGGGAUUACAGGCAUGUGCCACCACGCCUGGCUCACUUUUGUAUUUUUAGUAGAAAUGGGGUUUCACCAUAUUGGCCAGGCUGGUCUUGAACUCCUGACCUCAAAUGAUCCGCCUGCCAAUCCUCUCCCAAAGUGCUGGGAUUACAGGUGUGAGCCACCGUGCCUGGCCUCAACUCAGAGUGUUAGUAAUGCAGCCGGCAGUGAUGUCAAGAUGCGGACACAGGGACACUUGGAGGAUGGGAGCUUUGUCCCUUGUCCCCACCUGCUCCUCAGUAUCUCUUCAUGCCUUCAGGAGAGUUUUAAAGAUAACUGGGUUUUCAUAUUAGAAAUAGCCUGUUUUAUUCCAUUCUUGGACAAGAGUUUUGGCAUUGUUCCUAAAGUGUCAUAGUAAAGUGUAUAGGAAAGAGGGCUGUCAUUACUGUGGUAUAAGCUUUUCUGUGCCAUUAUUAAUAUAUGGGACAGAGCAUACUUUGUGAAAGUUAAAACUCACGCUUUAUCCAAGUUUUAAGGUAUCUGGUGAAUGCUAAUGAGUUUACAAAAAUUGUACAGUCUUAUGAAAUCUUGCAGUAUAAAUAAUCACAGGUGGUUUGUGAGUGUUUAAUGUAGAUGUAUCAAAAUUCCCAUGUCCUGGAGGAAGUUGAGAAUGCCAUUUGUGCAUAUGCGUAUGUAGAGGGGGCUUCAUAAUAUUCUUUCCCUUGUAACUUGAUUCUAUUUGAAACACAUAAAACUGGUCAGGGUUCUUUUUCAUUUUUUCUUUUUUUAGUGGAUGUGCAGGGUAAAGUAGUGUAUCGGAAAGAGAGAGGCCUAGACUUGAAAGAUUUUCAGACUUUUAAGCCUAAGCUUGCCAUGAAUGAGUAUAUGACUUUUGAGCAUGUCAUUAUUUCUGUUUCCCAGCGUCGUCUUCUAUAAAAUGGAAAUAGUCACACUCACCUACUUCUUAGAGUUGUCUUAGGGUGAGAUAGAAGCCUGCAUUCUUUAUGCCUGCUUGUCCUUCUAGGGAAUGCUCUGGAAUUGGAACAGCAUGUGGGCCACCCCUUAGGAUAGGUGACUCUUAGAAGGUGAGAGGAGGCAGGGCGUCGGGUGUGCAAGAGAAUCAGCUACAUCAUCUUUCAGGUUCCUGCUGCGGUGGGUGAAUUCUGUUAUUCUGUGCCCAUGGAAUGGGAGGUGUCAUAGAAGUCAUAGACAUCAGACGUAGAGUUUGACCUGAGUGAGUCAGUUGCCCUCUUGGGGUUUGCAUAUUCUUACCUGUGAAAUGCAGUAAUAAUACUGGUAAUAUUAUUAUUAUCAUCAAUGAACAGUUUUUAAUCAUCUUAUAUGUGACCAGGCAUGGUGUCAAGUUCUUUAUGACAUUUCUUCAUUCAUUCAGCAACUAUUUAAUGAAUGCUGCCAUAUGCCAGUCAUCGUUCCAGGCUCUGGGGAUCAGUGGGAUCACGGGCUAGCAUGGUGGCUGGGACAGACAGACUCCCUGCCUGCAUGGAGUUUAUAUGCUAGUGCAUGACAGAAGGUAAACAGAUACAUGGAUGAGGUGAUUCCCAUGGUCAGUGCUGUAAAGACAACUAAGUCAGUUCAGGGGGCUGGAGUCUGGUGGGAGAGCAGGUUGUGUUUUUAUUAGGAUGAGGCUCCUCCGAGGAGGAGAAUUUGAGAUCUGAGUGAGGCAAGGGGAUGAGCCUCGCAGAAACAAGUGCAAAUAUCAGCCCAGUGGCUGGCAGGAGCUUGCUAUGGAAGGAAUGGCCAGAGGGCCUGUGUGGGAGGAGCCAGCGGCCAGGGCAGGAAGAGAGCUGUGCAGUGGGGUCCAAGGAGGUCUGGCAGGCCACGGUGAGGACGUGGCUCAUGAGGAAGCCACAGGAGAGUUCUGAGCAGGGCGUGCAGGAGAUGGACCUUGUAUUUUGUCAGUGUGUCCCUGUGGUUGUGGAGGGCCACGGGGACUGCAGAGGGCCAGGAAUAGAAGCAGGGAGACCAGCCGGGGUGCCGCUGGUGAGAUGGAUUGGAGUUGAUACAAGAGAGAAAGGCAUUGUGGGUGACACCUGCUCUUUUGGCCUCAGCCUUUGGGUGAAAGAUGGUGCCAUUGAUUGAUAUGGGGAGACUGGUGGAGGAUGAGCUUUAUGAUGUUCACAUCAGCCUCUGGACUUAGUGUUGUUUUAUUCCCAUUUUACAGAUGUGGAGACCAAGGGGGAGAGAAGUAAAAAGUUUGCCCUAGGACCUGGCCAACAAGGAGAAUGCAGUUGAAACUAAUUUUGUGGAUAGAGAAACUGUUGGAACUGCUUUACAAAGUAUUUUAACAGCCCACCUGAGGAUAUUGACCAUAAGGACUCAUAUCUCAUUACAAGAAGCAUCAUGGCCGAGCCAGACUACAUAGAAGAUGACAAUCCUGAACUCAUUAGGCCUCAGAAACUGAUCAAUCCUGUAAAAACCUCCCGGAACCAUCAAGAUCUUCACAGAGAACUUCUUAUGAAUCAAAAAAGGGGUCUUGCUCCUCAGAACAAACCAGAAUUGCAGAAGGUGAUGGAAAAAAGAAAACGAGACCAAGUAAUAAAGCAGAAGGAAGAAGAAGCACAGAAGAAGAAAUCUGACUUGGAAAUAGAGCUAUUAAAACGGCAGCAGAAGUUGGAGCAGCUUGAACUUGAGAAGCAGAAAUUGCAAGAAGAGCAAGAAAAUGCCCCCGAGUUUGUGAAGGUGAAAGGCAAUCUCAGGAGAACAGGCCAAGAAGUCGCCCAAGCCCAGGAGUCCUAGGCUGAGGCUGCACCAAGACCUCGUGUGUCACCCCACAGAGCUGUCUGUGGGUGCCUUCUCAAUCUCAGGGCAAAAGCCCCUGGAGAAUAUUUCAGCCAGCAGAGAAUUUUGACUUGCAGUAGGAUUUGGUUUGAUUUUCCUACGAUCUGGGUGGAUGCCUUGCCUGUGACAGUUGCAGUUCCUAUUCGCCAAAUGAAGGGCAGUGCCCCGCACGUAAGUUGGAAUGAUGGACCUGUGUUCAGAGACUUAACAGAACCAACAAGCAAAACAAGUGAGAACAGGAAAAAGGAAGAGGACACUGGAAUCAAUUCUUGAGAGUUGCACUACUUGGUUUUUCUUCCAUUCCAAGUUUCGUGGGACCCAGAGCCUUUUUUCUUUUAAAAGCUAAAAAACAAGUGUUUAAUUCCUCUUUUUGUUAUCUGUUAGAUAAUUGAGAUCACCUAGAAAUGCGUUUAAUCUGUUCACUCACUGUAAAUUUUGAGGACCCAGAAUUGUCUUGUUUAAUUUAUACUUUCACCCCUGUUGCAGUUAACACCAGAGAAGGAACGUGAAUGUCGAGCACAGCCACUACCCUUGUUGGCACUUAAUUUAGAAAUAGGGUGAGAAGUUUAAAAGCCCAUCUUGAUUUUAUUUUCAUUCCUUUUGGUUCUCUGUGUAAUAAUAGCAGGCUACAUAGUGACAUUCCAGUUCCAAGAAGGUACAUCCUGUCCAUUCAUUAAUUGCUUUGAUUACUAGGAGGGUUUCUGUUCAGUUUUGUUUUUAAAUGUCUUGCUGAUCUAGUUCUUUCAGAUGGAAUAACCUUCCAGUCCCUUAGAGAGUGGAACUAGUCCAUAUAACCCAGCUUCAGUAGCAAAAGUAGAAGCCGCCACAUCUUUUCAUUUCUCCAAGAGGAGAGUGGGGAAGGUUCCCAUGACCAGCUGGGCAGUCAGGAUUUCUCUAGGCAUUCUAAUGUGAAAUAAGUGUAGACUGCUGUCAAGGAGGCUUCAUCAGAAGAUGUAUAGCAUUUGAAUGUCUAAUGAUAAUGCAUAUCAUUAGAAUCCAAGCUUUGAAAAUUUCUGAUUAAUGCUCAUGUAUUUCUUUAUCUUUGUUUUUCCUUGUGAAGAAAGACUUUCACCACUGUCUGAGUGAUGAUGCUGUUGAUAAGGAUGAUGUCGAUGACUACUAUAUUGCAUCUCUCAGGAACAGCUGAUGGGAAGGGAGGGGCUGCUGAGUUCCCUUGUUCUAGCUAGCAGCACGCUCCUCAGAGAGGGGGCCGAGUUACAGACAGCAGCCGCAUUCUCAUGCAAAAUUAGUUUUAAACUGCUAGUGUGGGCAUCGGUACCUUUUGCCUGGGUGAUACCGAAGAAUUGUUGAGGAUUUAGUAUGCUCCGUAGAGACAGUUCAGCCAGUCAUUUCUGCAUUGGAGAGACUUCUCAUACUUUCUUUGAAGACUCAUAGAAAGCUGGAUCUAGAGCUUUUGAAUCCUUAAUUAGCACAGUAGAAAUUAGCUUUCUAUGGGAAUGCUUUAGUGUUAGCAGUUGACAAUUAGGCCCAUAUUCAAUCUGAAUGGGAACAAAAGUAAAUGCAAUGAUAAUAUACUGCUAGUUAGAGAAACAUGUUAGUUGAUUAUACCUGAAAUGGAUUAUUUAUCUCAUCAGCAAGUAUUAUUUGAAUAAAAUGAGAAAUGCUUAAGAAAAAUUGUUGCUCUACAGUAAUUUGGUUUCGAAGAAUGGAAUGGUAACUAUUUUUUCCCAUCGUUCUUUUGAGAGAAGGAAGUGUGAUGACUGAUGAUCUUGAAAAGCCCAUUUCUGAUUGCACGUUGACUGGAAUUCUUUCUUUGUGUCUGUGGACUAGCGAUGCUGUUUGUAAAAUGAAGAUUCGGGACUGGCUCAUAUCUUUUUAUCUAACUAGAUGUCAGAUCUUGAAAUCUGUAUUCUCGAAGCAAUUCUGCCACUUGAUCGUAUUCACAGGGGCCCUGGUAGGCUCCUUUAGAAGGACCAUUUCUGUUCCUAGAGCUUAACUAGAAUUCAUUCUUCACUGAAAAAAAAAAAAGUUACUUAAGAAAGCAUUUCUUUCCUAAUCUCACUCAAAUCUGCAGAAUUAUUUGUAAUUAGUAAUACAAAAUCUGGCCAAAAGGAGACUUGUAAAUAGCGUAAAGUGGUGUCUUAUGCUAAACGGUGGAAUGUAUAGGCAGAGAAGCUCUUUGAAGUUGUCAGAUGAGCUGGGCUCACAAGCCUGAUUCAAACAGGCUGUCGGUCUCCUCUCACCCCUUAAUACUGUGCAGCCCAAACUCCUAGGACUCUUGAACAUCUGAGCAGUUUUGUGCUUUGAGCCACUUUUUGACAAAAAUGGCUCCAUUUUUCCACAGCGUGGUUUUCUUAAAAUAGUUUAAUGUUUUAUAGUCUCAUAGUAGUAGUGUUGCUUUCUAAGCUAUAACAGUCGACUUUAUUCUUCUACUCUGAAAAAUCUUGACUUGUUUGAGUGUAUAUAAUAUAUAUAAAGGGAGCCUUAAUGGAUUGGUUUUCAUAAUUUAAUAUUUUUUGUAUUUGCUCUUGUAUAAUUGUUUUUAACGGAAAGUAUUAAAGAAUUGAGGGUGGAAUUCUUAGAACCAAAGUUAUUCUUAAUAAAAAUCACCACAUGCUUGGACCAUGCAA